ACACUUUGCUGCCGAAACGAAGCCAGACAACAGAUUUCCAUCAGCAGGAUGUGGGGGCUCAAGGUUCUGCUGCUACCUGUGGUGAGCUUUGCUCUGUACCCUGAGGAGAUACUGGACACCCACUGGGAGCUAUGGAAGAAGACCCACAGGAAGCAAUAUAACAACAAGGUGGAUGAAAUCUCUCGGCGUUUAAUUUGGGAAAAAAACCUGAAGUAUAUUUCCAUCCAUAACCUUGAGGCUUCUCUUGGUGUCCAUACAUAUGAACUGGCUAUGAACCACCUGGGGGACAUGACCAGUGAAGAGGUGGUUCAGAAGAUGACUGGACUCAAAGUACCCCUGUCUCAUUCCCGCAGUAAUGACACCCUUUAUAUCCCAGAAUGGGAAGGUAGAGCCCCAGACUCUGUCGACUAUCGAAAGAAAGGAUAUGUUACUCCUGUCAAAAAUCAGGGUCAGUGUGGUUCCUGUUGGGCUUUUAGCUCUGUGGGUGCCCUGGAGGGCCAACUCAAGAAGAAAACUGGCAAACUCUUAAAUCUGAGUCCCCAGAACCUAGUGGAUUGUGUGUCUGAGAAUGAUGGCUGUGGAGGGGGCUACAUGACCAAUGCCUUCCAAUAUGUGCAGAAGAACCGGGGUAUUGACUCUGAAGAUGCCUACCCAUAUGUGGGACAGGAAGAGAGUUGUAUGUACAACCCAACAGGCAAGGCAGCUAAAUGCAGAGGGUACAGAGAGAUCCCCGAGGGGAAUGAGAAAGCCCUGAAGAGGGCAGUGGCCCGAGUGGGACCUGUCUCUGUGGCCAUUGAUGCAAGCCUGACCUCCUUCCAGUUUUACAGCAAAGGUGUGUAUUAUGAUGAAAGCUGCAAUAGCGAUAAUCUGAACCAUGCAGUUUUGGCAGUGGGAUAUGGAAUCCAGAAGGGAAACAAGCACUGGAUAAUUAAAAACAGCUGGGGAGAAAACUGGGGAAACAAAGGAUAUAUCCUCAUGGCUCGAAAUAAGAACAACGCCUGUGGCAUUGCCAACCUGGCCAGCUUCCCCAAGAUGUGACUCCAGCCAGCCAAAUCCAUCCUGCUCUUCCAUUUCUUCCACGAUGGUGCAGUGUAACGAUGCACUUUGGAAGGGAGUUGGUGUGCUAUUUUUGAAGCAGAUGUGGUGAUACUGAGAUUGUCUGUUCAGUUUCCCCAUUUGUUUGUGCUUCAAAUGAUCCUUCCUACUUUGCUUCUCUCCACCCAUGACCUUUUUCACUGUGGCCAUCAGGACUUUCCCUGACAGCUGUGUACUCUUAGGCUAAGAGAUGUGACUACAGCCUGCCCCUGACUGUGUUGUCCCAGGGCUGAUGCUGUACAGGUACAGGCUGGAGAUUUUCACAUAGGUUAGAUUCUCAUUCACGGGACUAGUUAGCUUUAAGCACCCUAGAGGACUAGGGUAAUCUGACUUCUCACUUCCUAAGUUCCCUUCUAUAUCCUCAAGGUAGAAAUGUCUAUGUUUUCUACUCCAAUUCAUAAAUCUAUUCAUAAGUCUUUGGUACAAGUUUACAUGAUAAAAAGAAAUGUGAUUUGUCUUCCCUUCUUUGCACUUUUGAAAUAAAGUAUUUAUCUCCUGUCUACAGUUUAAUAAAUAGCAUCUAGUACACAUUCA